GCACUAGAGGCGACCUAAACAUGGAGACAGCGGGCGCUGCAACUGGGCAGCCGGCCUCUGGGCUGGAGGCUCCGGGGUCCACGAAUGACCGGCUUUUCCUGGUUAAAGGUGGAAUUUUCCUUGGUACCGUUGCUGCAGCGGGAAUGCUAGCUGGAUUUAUUACAACAUUAUCAUUGGCUAAAAAGAAAAGCCCUGAAUGGUUCAAUAAGGGAAGUAUGGCCACGGCUGCAUUACCGGAAAGCGGGUCUUCCCUUGCCUUGCGAGCUCUGGGCUGGGGCUCCCUGUAUGCAUGGUGUGGGGUUGGUGUGAUUAGCUUCGCAGUCUGGAAAGCUUUAGGAGUUCACAGUAUGAACGACUUUCGAAGUAAAAUGCAAUCAAUAUUUCCAACAAUUCCCAAGAACUCCGAAUCGGCUGUUGAGUGGGAGGAAACAUUGAAAUCCAAAUGAGAUGAGCAUGGAUGAAUUUCAAAAUGCUUGUUACAGAAAGGGGUGGCUCUGGAGACACCAUGACAGCAAAAGGACUGGGACUGAUUUCUCCCAGGAACAUGGGCAGAUUGCUGACUGAACCAGUGCACUGGAUAGCAUUCAGCCUCAUCACAGGAGAGUAUGUGUGUGCGUGCUGGGGGAGGGUAAAGUUUUCCCACAGUUAAGAAGACUAUUUAAAAAUAGUAAUUACAGGAAUAACUUCCUUAUGUGGAGGGGACCCCAUAGGAAAUGAUUCUGUUUGUAACAGUUGAAGCAAAUUUCAUACUAAAAAAGUUUAUAAUAAAAGUAUGAUAAGAAAAUAUUUAUAAAACAGACCCCCUAAUAGCAAUAGUACUGCAAUGUGUCUAAUUAAAGGAGUUUCAAGAGCCUUUCUUGUCAAUAUAUGACAGAACUUGGAAGUCUUAUUCUGAUUAGCCAGACUACAAAGUGACAGUCACCUGGUAAGUCCUGUAUGGUAGGAAGUGGGUGUGGCUCUCGGGUCCUAAAUGUGGUCUGUGCUUUACAGCCAUCACACACAUGCUAGUUAUUUACCUGAUGCCCUUGCUUGAAGGCCCUAUAAAUUCUUAUACUUAAAACAAAAAGCCAGUAAUGAGUUGUGAUCACCCCAAAAGGCACAGUUGGGCUAAAAUAAUGAUGAUAUCAGGGGUAAACAUAUUUUUUUGAGAAGUUGGUCUGGAUCUCUGAACACUGACAAUUUGUCAUUUUGUCUCAGUUGUCAAAGUAAAAAAAGCCCAGUUGUCAUCCGUCUUCAAUAUUUUUAACCAGAAAGUCACCUGAGUACGGAGUCCCAAUAUAAAGUAUUUGGGACCACCUCCCUAACAAAGCUGUUAGGGUAAAUUCUGUGUGCACGCCCAACUCCCUCCUGUCUUCCACAGUCUCCUACAAAAAAAACAGAUGGAGAAUAAUGUCUACAUGCAAUUGUUUUUACUGCAAUUGUAUUUUAAAAUAUUUUCAAGAAGAGAAAUACUUUAAUAUGUCAAUAUGUCCAGAGAAAAAACCUGUAGUUAAAUAUCAGUUGUGCAAUUUCUUCCUACUUGCCUAGGCUCUAAUUAGUCAGCAAUCAGGUUUAAUAAAGGACAUUUGAAAUUUCUGUUAUCAUGAAACCUUUUAUUCUAAGGGAGAUUUUUAAAUGAAAUGACAAGAACUUAAUGUAAUACUUUUCUCUAGACCAUGUUACCCUGUUAAAAUUGCUGUAUUGUUAAUGAAACAGGUGUAAUCAGCAUCUGGAAUUCAUAUGUAAUCUGUUAAAAAUCCAAGACUGAAAGGAAAGGAUUGUGAAAUUGGUCAGUGAAUGCGGGUAGCAAAAACUCUUCACUGCCUUUCAUUUGUAACUAAAUCUCCUCUGAGAAGAGAUCUGUAGGCUUUGAAUGAAAGGAAGGAAAGGCAGGAGCCAAAGGAACAGGUUUUCGUCCAUACAAUUAGUCUGAAUCUAGGUUCCUCUGAAUAGAAUGGGCACCGCCUGAUCCUUUUGUGCUUCAUAAAUGUGGGUUUCCAACGUGCAUGAGAUGGCCCUCAAACCUUGUUACAACGAUGCACUUUACUCGUUUGAUGUGGGGGGAAAAAGAAUGGGCACUACCUAAAACUGUUUACAGCUAGAAUCUGGGUUUUAUUUUUCAUAGAUGGAGAAUGCCUAGUGGUUUCUAAAGGCCUCCACUGGGUGGAGAAAGGAGACUUGCCCACCUGUCUGGAGUGUUAAAAGGAGAAAUCAUUGUUAACUGAUUCUGUUAAUGGAUUCCUGCCUUGUAACCUCCCGAAGGGCAGGGACCCCUCUCAGGGCCUUGUAAACUGGUGUCAGCACCGCUGCAGAGGCUGCUGCACAUCAGGCUGAUGGCAGCUAGGCCCUAGGAAGGAGCCAGGGGCCAUGGUGGGGGCUCUGCUUUCCCACAGGGCUGGCACAGAGGAGGCCUAGACAUAUGUUGCUGAAAGAGUGUCCUAAUACUAGAGUGGCAUGCCUCGUGUCUACAAAACCCUUAUAUGUCACCUCUGCUGUCCUUGACCGAUGGCAGGGGAACUCCCAUUAGAAUGAUGAUGAAUCCCCUGCAGAGGGGAGGCUGGCAGGGACAAAUUCCCUAAAAGAGGGACCAAGCGUCAGCUCCAAUUGCAUCUUAAAAGCAAAGGUGAAGUAAUGCACAGAUGGAAAUUUAAAAAGAAAACAAGCAGUAUGACUCAAGUGGUGUUUUUCACAGUCAGAACUUGAAUAUCAGUAGAUUUCGUCAUUUGUCUAUUCCUUUUGUACCAGAGGCAUAUUGUUAAAUUGGUUAAUGGAAAGGAAAAAUGUUGAACAGAUAAUGUUAUUCUUUAUGAGACGUACCAUCUGUGUAUUGAGCUCUGAAUGUCCCUGGAUAUGGAAGAGAGGAAAUGUGAUGGAAUUUCAAGUUUGCCUUCUUUGCUGUCUUUAUCUUGGGUUGAGUAUGACAAACAUAAUCACAUUUAUCUCCUGGAGCAUAAAGAGUUUUAAUCACCCUAUUAACCAGGAUGACAUUUUUCACAGACUUAAAAAGGAAUAGAACAGACAUUAUCUCCCUAUAAGCAAUCCAUUUCAUGGAGGCUGAGCACUAGAAAUGCUUUAAAGGAUGGAUAACGCAGGCCAUUUCCAUUUCCUGUCUAAGCCAACAUUAAGGAGGCUUUCGGUAAGGCUGUUGCUUCCACUGGGUGAGUGUUAAGCUUUACACUUAGAGUCUCAGCGCCCAAAAGAGCUAUUAGAGAAAGCACGGGCAGGGAGGAGUGGCUUCCGAGACCCCAGGAUUCAUUCAAGGGAAAACAUGUAUCCUGGUAAGUUGCUGCUGCCCUGUGAAAAGGAGUCCAUAGGCUGCUGUUAUAUUCAGAGUCAAGAAAGUGUGGGUUCAGGACAACCUGAGAGUGGAAAGUGGGGGACGGGAGCUGCCUCCGAAGACGCCCGGCAGCCCAUCACCAGGAGGACCAUGGCCCAAGGGCAUGGAAGCAUGUGGCUGCUGAGAGGGUCGUGGGCCAUCUCCACCACCACCCUCGCGUCAGGGCAUGGGCCCAGGCUGGCGUUAAGGGCACUUUGCCUGCUUAGUCAAAAGGUGGCAUCGAAUCACCUGGGCUGUCACAUGUUUUGUUUAGUUUCAUGGAUAGUAUGGGACCAAACUUGCAAAUUAAUCAUUGCAAUCUAAGGGGAAAAUAGAAGAAAUUAAGGUGGGGGUGGGGGGACGGGGAGCCCAUGGGGAUAAAAGUAAUUAAAAUCCAUUGAAUUUAGCUAUUUCACUUGGGGCAACAUUUAAUCUCCAAGAUUAAAUCUUGGUUUAUGGGGAAGGUUAUAUAUUUUCAUCUCAUUUUUAUGUAUCAUCUUUAAGACAAAUUGUUAAGUACAAAUGAAAAUCAGGUAACAUACAAAGGCAUUUCAUCAAAUAGUUAAAUUUCCUAUGAAAGUUAGUAAAAUACAUAUUUUUAUAAUACCAUGUUCAAGUGAAGUGUUUUUGCUUUCUGCCAAGAGUCAUUAAAUGAUAUAGCAAGUAUUUGGGUCUCUCUUGGUGUUAUCAGGAUUAAUUGCCCAAGGCUGCGAUUUUGUGAGCAUAGAAGAGGAAAGCAAGCAUCUCUCACAAGCAGUGACAUGAAUCUGUAAUAAUGAGUGAGGCUGUUAGCAAAUUUUGUGUGAUGGCAGAUAACUCAGUUUUGGAGAAAAUUAGAAUCACAGCUACCAAGAAGCACAUAUCGUUUCAACUUUCCCACCCAAGUAUUAGUGAAGUGAUUUAGGACCUUGAUUUAUAUUUCUUAGAGAAGCUGGCUCGAGGCCUUUGUUUCAUUACUGUUUGAUGAGGCAUGAUCCCUUACUUUAAAAAAAAAAAAAGGUGAAUGUAUUAAAUGUACUUAAAGACA